GGGCAGAAGGAUGGGCCGAGAUUAACGGUGUGAAUGUGACUGACGAUUCCUGUGCUGAGGCCUCUGCUGGACUUAAGAAAGUCAGCUGAGGAGUUCAGGCCCUGUGCCUGGCUCAAAGGCCCAGGGACCCAGGCCCUUAGCUUCUGCCCUGCUCUCUGGAUGGAGGCUGUGGGACUGCUCUGUGCAGUGUGAAGCCUCCAUCCGCUACACAGGUCCAAGUGGGUGGCAGGGGGAGCGAGAAUGCCUGAUUCUGGACUCCUUGGUUAGGCUCCCUGGGUUCUAAUCCCAGUUUUGCCAAUUCCUAGCUGUGUGACCUUGGGCAAGUUGCUUAACAUUUCUUUCUGGGCCUUAGUUUCCUCAUUGGUAAAAUGUGCAUAAUAAUAAUCCCUUCCUCAUAACAUUGUGAGGCUGAAAUGAGAAAAUGCAUGUAAAGUGCUUAAUGUAUCUGGCACAUGUUGUUUAACAAAUAUUAGCUGCUGUUGUUAUUGCUAAUAAUAGUAAUAUGCCCACUUCUGGGUAGGGAUAUUGGCCAAUGCAGAGCUUGUACUCAGGAGGCCACCAGGACCUGUCACGCAGAGGGCCUGUCAGCGGUGUCCUGUUGCAAGGGGCAGUUUAUUAAGAAAAGACUAAAAUACUUGCUAGGAAGGACUAGAAUGAGGCUUCCUGUGGGCCAGUGCAGGGGACAGAGCUGGGAUCCAGGGCUGGGGACUUUUAGAGUCAGGGAUGUGAUUCAACAUAAGGAAGAACCUCUGCUCUGGCUCUUGGAUCUGCCGCCAAAUGGAAGGGACAGCUCCUGAGCUGGAAUGCUCUCCCCACCUAGCUGACCUUCCUCCCAGCACAGCUCCAAUGCAGGCAUGUGCAUCCACCACCCUUCCACGCACACUUACUGAGCACCUGCCAGUGCUGAGCAGGGUUUAGAGACUGCAGACUCUGCAGUGAUUGAGAUGGACAGCGUCCUUAGAUUCUGGUUGGGUAGACAGGUGAUAAACCAGUGAACAGAUGUGAACAUUAGACCUAUGAUGAAUAAAAUCAGGCUAGUGUGGUGGGGUGGGGAUGCAAGCUGUUCAGGGAAGUGACAUGGGAAUGGAAACCUGGUUGAUGAGAAAGAGCCAGUUCUGGGCAGAGGGAAUGGCAGAUGCAGAGGCCCUGAGUGGGGAGAGAAGGCCCACGUGAUGGGACCAUAGUGAGUGGCUGGGAAAUGAGGUUGGUGGGGAGCAGGAGCUGGGGACUGAAGUCUGGCCUGAUGGUCCACCCCAUUUUGGGGGCCACUUUCUCCUCCUCCAAGCCCACUCAGCCUUUGGUUUGCUCUCUGCACAGUGCAGACUGUACUUGACCUUGGUUCAUCCCUUAUCAGCUCCUGGGGCUCUGGGAUCUUGGUGUGCUCAUUCUUGCCUCUCCUGUUGUUCGGGGCACACUGCCUGGCUCCCGGGGGUCCUCAGUAAAUGCUUGUGAUGUGACUAUUGAGGGGGGCAUUUUGAUCUGGAACAAGUGGGGAAACAGAUACCUGUUUGAAGAUGCUAUGAAUCAUUUGUGGGCACCACCUGGUGCCAAACUCUGGCCCCCGUUCUGAGAACCAGAUGGGGAAGACCUGGGCACUCAGGUUGGGCCUGACUAUGGUAGGUGGUAUUUGGCCCUCCCUACCCUUCCUCCUCAGCAGUGGGGUGGUAGGGAGAAAAGACAAAGCUGGGGGAAACUACAGACCAGUUUCGGGGGGAUGGGAGGAUGACACUGUCAUCCUGGAAAGCAGGUGUAGUCCAUGGGCCGGGGCAGGUUGGAAACCUUGUCUUGCUUUCUGUUUGGGGUUAAAGGUGCUCCAGAUGUUCCAGUCUGCCCUCCCUUCCCUCCUUGUCUCCUGUGGCCUUUUCCUGCUUCCCAUCAUACCCACAGGAUCGGGAGGGAGGGGUGCUGACAAUGUUGUAAGGGGAGAGCCUGGGUACUGUGGGCCAGAGGAUCUUCCCUUGGCCUGUAGACCUUGGGCAAAGGUCAGGUGGGUGAGGAAGCCCAUUGCCCACCCUCUGGGGUCCUCCUCCUCUUUGCCCCUCCUAGCUCCCAUCAUCUCCUUCUCUUUUCCCAGACCUCAUCUCAGUCUGAAGGGCAGUCCAAUAGCCAGUGAAGGCCUGGUCCUGCCCUCACUCUGGUGCGUAGUCGAGAGGAGAGAGCACUGGAGGGGAUGGAAGAAGAGAAGGGGAGAUGUGGGUCAAGGCCUCCACCAUGGACAGAGGCCAGGCCCUGCCCCUCCCAGGCAGCCUGGCUCCUUCUGCUGGGCCCUGAAGGCAGACGGGAUAAUGUGGUUGGCCAAGGCCUGUUGGUCCAUCCAGAGUGAGAUGCCCUGUAUCCAAGCCCAAUAUGGGACACCAGCACCGAGUCCGGGACCCCGUGACCACCUGGCAAGCGACCCCCUGACCCCUGAGUUCAUCAAGCCCACCAUGGACCUGGCCAGCCCCGAGGCAGCCCCCGCUGCCCCCACUGCCCUGCCCAGCUUCAGCACCUUCAUGGACGGCUACACAGGAGAGUUUGACACCUUCCUCUACCAGCUGCCAGGAACAGUCCAGCCAUGCUCCUCAGCCUCCUCCUCGGCCUCCUCCACAUCCUCGUCCUCAGCCACCUCCCCUGCCUCUGCCUCCUUCAAGUUCGAGGACUUCCAGGUGUACGGCUGCUACCCCGGCCCCCUGAGCGGCCCAGUGGAUGAGGCCCUGUCCUCCAGUGGCUCUGACUACUAUGGCAGCCCCUGCUCGGCCCCGUCGCCCUCCACGCCCAGCUUCCAGCCGCCCCAGCUCUCUCCCUGGGAUGGCUCCUUCGGCCACUUCUCGCCCAGCCAGACUUACGAAGGCCUGCGGGCAUGGACAGAGCAGCUGCCCAAAGCCUCUGGGCCCCCACAGCCUCCAGCCUUCUUUUCCUUCAGUCCUCCCACCGGCCCCAGCCCCAGCCUGGCCCAGAGCCCCCUGAAGUUGUUCCCCUCACAGGCCACCCACCAGCUGGGGGAGGGAGAGAGCUAUUCCAUGCCUACGGCCUUCCCAGGUUUGGCACCCACUUCUCCACACCUUGAGGGCUCGGGGAUACUGGAUACACCCGUGACCUCAACCAAGGCCCGGAGCGGGGCCCCAGGUGGAAGUGAAGGCCGCUGUGCUGUGUGUGGGGACAACGCUUCAUGCCAGCAUUAUGGUGUCCGCACAUGUGAGGGCUGCAAGGGCUUCUUCAAGCGCACAGUGCAGAAAAACGCCAAGUACAUCUGCCUGGCUAACAAGGACUGCCCUGUGGACAAGAGGCGGCGAAACCGCUGCCAGUUCUGCCGCUUCCAGAAGUGCCUGGCGGUGGGCAUGGUGAAGGAAGUUGUCCGAACAGACAGCCUGAAGGGGCGGCGGGGCCGGCUACCUUCAAAACCCAAGCAGCCCCCAGAUGCCUCCCCUGCCAAUCUCCUCACUUCCCUGGUCCGUGCACACCUGGACUCAGGGCCCAGCACUGCCAAACUGGACUACUCCAAGUUCCAGGAGCUGGUGCUGCCCCACUUUGGGAAGGAAGAUGCUGGGGAUGUACAGCAGUUCUACGACCUGCUCUCCGGUUCUCUGGAGGUCAUCCGCAAGUGGGCGGAGAAGAUCCCUGGCUUUGCUGAGCUGUCACCGGCUGACCAGGACCUGUUGCUGGAGUCGGCCUUCCUGGAGCUCUUCAUCCUCCGCCUGGCGUACAGGUCUAAGCCAGGCGAGGGCAAGCUCAUCUUCUGCUCAGGCCUGGUGCUACACCGGCUGCAGUGUGCCCGUGGCUUCGGGGACUGGAUUGACAGUAUCCUGGCCUUCUCAAGGUCCCUGCACAGCUUGCUUGUCGAUGUCCCUGCCUUCGCCUGCCUCUCUGCCCUUGUCCUCAUCACCGACCGGCAUGGGCUGCAGGAGCCGCGGCGGGUGGAGGAGCUGCAGAACCGCAUCGCCAGCUGCCUGAAGGAGCACGUGGCAGCUGUGGCGGGCGAGCCCCAGCCAGCCAGCUGCCUGUCACGUCUGUUGGGCAAACUGCCCGAGCUGCGGACCCUGUGCACCCAGGGCCUGCAGCGCAUCUUCUACCUCAAGCUGGAGGACUUGGUGCCCCCUCCACCCAUCAUUGACAAGAUCUUCAUGGACACGCUGCCCUUCUGACCCCUGCCUGGGAACACGUGUGCACAUGCGCACUCUCAUAUGCCACCCCAUGUGCCUUUAGUCCACGGACCCCCAGAGCACCCCCAAGCCUGGGCUUGAGCUGCAGAAUGACUCCACCUUCUCACCUGCUCCAGGAGGUUUGCAGGGAGCUCAAGCCCUUGGGGAGGGGGAUGCCUUCAUGGGGGUGACCCCACGAUUUGUCUUAUCCCCCCCAGCCUGGCCCCGGCCUUUAUGUUUUUUGUAAGAUAAACCGUUUUUAACACAUAGCGCCGUGCUGUAAAUAAGCCCAGUGCUGCUGUAAAUACAGGAAGAAAGAGCUUGAGGUGGGAGCGGGGCUGGGAGGAAGGGAUGGGCCCCGCCUUCCUGGGCAGCCUUUCCAGCCUCCUGCUGGCUCUCUCUUCCUACCCUCCUUCCACAUGUACAUAAACUGUCACUCUAGGAAGAAGACAAAUGACAGAUUCUGACAUUUAUAUUUGUGUAUUUUCCUGGAUUUAUAGUAUGUGACUUUUCUGAUUAAUAUAUUUAAUAUAUUGAAUAAAAAAUAGACAUGUAGUUGGAA